GAGGGGGCAGAGGGCAGAACCAAGGGAAGGGGACGCUGUCAGGCCCAGGCCCCUGGGGGGCCAGGGCCAGGCCACUGCCUGGGGGCAGCAGGCAUCAGAAACUAAAGUAGGAUGAAUCACCCACUUGACUCUCUUCUUCCUGGGGCGAUACCAAGCUUUAGGAUCCCCUGGGGGAAAGCAAAACCAGAAGAAGAGGGUGGCCAGGGGCUUGAGGCUGGGAGUCCUGCUGGUUCAGCAGGCAGCCUGCAGAAAAGGUAUGAGCUCUUACUGGGUCUGUAAUGUGCCUAAGGAGUUUGGGGGAGGGAGGCUGGAAAAGGGGGAAGUGAAAACCACCCAGAAGGGAAGGACUGGUCUACACCCUCCCCCAGGCCCACAGGGCACUGUGCUCCAUUGCUCUGGAGCCAGCAGGGGAAGUGUGUACACUAUGUGCACUGAGGGUGACACUUCUGAGUGUGGGGGCCCUGGCUAGGGAGUGGGACUGGCAGGCUUGGGUGGGGUUCCCAAGCUUUAAUCUUCCUACCCCACAGAAUGUUUUCUCUGCCCUUCAGGCAGCCUGAGCCGGGCAGGGCCCCUGCCUCUGCUACGGCAGCCCCCGAUCAUGCAGCCCCCACUGGACCUCAAGCAGAUCCUGCCCUUCCCACUCGAGCCAGCCCCUACCCUUGGCCUCUUCAGCAACUACAGCACCAUGGACCCUGUGCAGAAGGCUGUGCUCUCCCACACUUUUGGGGGACCCUUGCUCAAGACCAAGCGGCCCGUCAUUUCCUGUAAUAUCUGUCAAAUCCGCUUCAAUUCUCAGAGCCAGGCUGAGGCGCACUACAAAGGUAAUCGCCACGCCCGACGAGUCAAAGGCAUUGAGGCUGCCAAGACCAGAGGCAGGGAGCCUGGCGUCCGAGAACCUGGAGACCCAGCUCCCCCAGGCAGCACCCCAACAAAUGGGGAUGGUGUAGCACCCCGUCCAGUUUCCAUGGAGAAUGGACUGGGGCCAGCCCCAGGAUCCCCAGAGAAACAGCCUGGCUCCCCAUCCCCUCCCAGCAUUCCGGAGACUGGUCAGGGUGUAACCAAGGGUGAAGGGGGGACUCCAGCCCCGGCUUCCUUGCCUGGGGGUAGCAAGGAAGAGGAGGAGAAAGCCAAGCGGCUGCUCUACUGUGCUCUGUGCAAGGUGGCUGUGAACUCCCUGUCCCAGCUUGAGGCACAUAACAAAGGUACUAAGCACAAGACAAUUCUGGAGGCCCGAAGUGGGCUCGGGCCCAUCAAAGCUUACCCUCGGCUGGGGCCUCCCACCCCGGGGGAACCAGAGGCUCCUGCCCAGGACCGAACUUUCCACUGUGAGAUCUGCAAUGUCAAGGUCAACUCGGAGGUCCAACUGAAACAGCACAUCUCCAGCCGGCGGCACCGAGACGGCGUGGCCGGGAAGCCCAACCCACUACUGAGCCGUCACAAGAAGUCUAGGGGCGCCGGGGAGCUGGCGGGCACGCUGACUUUCUCCAAGGAGCUGCCCAAGUCCCUGGCGGGCGGCCUGCUCCCCAGCCCCCUGGCGGUGGCUGCAGUGAUGGCAGCGGCAGCAGGCUCGCCGCUGUCCCUGCGCCCGGCUCCAGCCGCACCUCUUCUCCAGGGACCGCCGAUCACUCACCCUCUGCUUCACCCGGCCCCCGGACCCAUCCGAACUGCGCACGGACCCAUCCUCUUCUCCCCGUACUGACCUCAACCCUGAACCCCUCCCAUUCAACUCCCCACCUCCAGCCGGGACCCAGGCGUCCGGGCUCCCAGCCCGCCCCUCCUCCCGGCACUCCCUAAAUGAUCUCUCCUUCCCCCCCCCCACCCCGAGAUACGGGGUUCCAGGAAAGGGGAGGGGUAGCGGGGGAGGGGGGCUUCAGAAGGGGGGGAACACCCCAGAUCUCAGGGAACCCCGCCCCCUGCCUUUCCCUCUCCCCUAGAAAAGGGGGGGCCGUCUCACCCCCGAGCCCCCUUGGAGACACCCCCCCUCCCAAAAGCCAUGUCCAUCCAGCCCUUCCCCCCAAACCUAGCACAAAACGGGGUUCACAAGCCAUGGUCGGGGUCCGGGGGGGACAGAAAUGGAUUUUCUUGGCAAUAAGCGGACUCUGGGACUCCGGCUCCCUACCCCAAACUGAAGCGCUUCCGUGAACACCCCCGUCCUCCGUAGGGGGAGGGGAGCAGGCGGGAUCCUGGGUCCCUCAUAAGCACUUUGGUUUUACCGCCUGCAACCUCACUGUGCCCGCCCCGCACCAUGCCCUAGCCCCAGGUCUAGCCGGGCCCAUUGCAGGGGGCAGCACUUGGGGGCAUCUCCGGCACUUGGGUGGGACCAAGGAGAUGCCACCAUAGACCUUUCCCUCGCCUUCUUCCUCCCUAGUCCGGGUUCCAUUCUUUUCACCAGCACCCAUCGCCCAAGGGGUACCGAGGGGGGCAAGGGGUGUCCAGUCCAAGCCCACCCCCGCCUCGCCUUCCGCAAAACUGUGAGCAAAAAGCAAUAGAAGCCUCGCCCCCGCCCUUCCCCUUCGCAGGAUUCGCCGAGUCUGUAGCCUCCCCGAUCCAAGUUCCUAGACCUCAUGGCUGUCCCCUCCCACCAGUCACCUCCACUGCACAACUCGGGCGGGGGUGUGACACCUCUCCCCCACCCCCGACUCCGUGGUUUCCGUAUCGUCAACCCUUCAGCCGCCGACCCGGGAGGGGUCUGGCCUACACUGGUCUUCCCCUUCCCAUCAACUCUUUCUGCUUGACAAUGUAGCAACCCAGGCCCCCCACCCACGGUCCUCCCCUUUUUCCUCUCCCUGACAAUAAAGUCUGAAUUUGUUCUGCCCUCC